GAAAGCAUCGGGUCUCGGGACUUCUGAGUGGCCUGGGUUACCGCGCGAUCUACACUGAGACAAGGAAGUUGGAAAAGCCGAGUAGUUAUACCAGAAGAUCAGGGUCUCACAGACUCGCAACUUCUCUUCCAUUUUCCCCAAUGGCGCAUGUCUUACAAAAUGUUUCACUUCAAGCCCACUACGGUGGUGACAAGCUGCCAGCCGAAGAAUCCAAGAGAACUACAUAGAAGGCGGAAGUUGGACCCUGGGAAGAUGCAUGCCAAAAUCUGGUUAAUGAAGACCUCGCUCAGGAGCGGGAGGGCCGCUCUGCGAGAGCUCCGAAGCCGUGAGAACUUCCUCAGCAAGCUCAACCGGGAGCUGAUCGAGACCAUCCAGGAGAUGGAGAACAGCACGACCCUGCACGUGCGGGCCCUGCUGCAGCAGCAGGACACCCUGGCGACCAUCAUCGACAUCUUGGAGUACUCAAACAAGAAGAGGCUGCAGCAAUUGAAAUCUGAGCUUCAGGAGUGGGAAGAAAAGAAGAAAUGCAAGAUGAGCUAUCUUGAGCAGCAGGCAGAGCAGCUGAAUGCCAAGAUUGAGAAGACCCAGGAGGAAGUGAACUUCCUGAGCACUUACAUGGACCAUGAGUAUUCCAUCAAGUCUGUCCAGAUCUCCACUCUUAUGCGCCAGCUGCAGCAGGUUAAGGACAGCCAGCAGGAUGAGCUGGAUGACCUCGGUGAGAUGCGCAGAAAGGUCCUGGAAUCCUUGUCUGACAAGAUUCAGAAGAAGAAGAAAAAAAUUCUGAGUUCUGUGGUGGCGGAAACCCAGCGUCCCUAUGAAGAGGCUCUCCUACAGAAGAUGUGGGAAAGCCAGGACUUCCUGAAAUGCAUGCAAAGGUUCAGAGAAGUGCGUGGGCAAGGAAGGUGGUGGUCCCUGUAGGGAAGCAGUGGAUGGGCAGUCCCCACGGCCUGUGGGAAUGAGUCAGGCUUCUCCUGAUCUGGCGCUCAGGAGGUCUCUGACUCUGGUGUUGGCCUCCCUCCUUGCCGGUGCCAUUACUGUCACUUGUCUUUCAUCUGGGAAGGCGAUUGGCACUGACCUAGGCCUUGCCUCAUUAGCCAGCAAUGCUGGCUAAUGACCCAUUUACAACCAUCACCAAACAUCACCUAUUCAGCCAUUAACCACCGUGCAUCUUUACCCCUUGAUUCUUGUUACUGCCCACCACCCAUUAUCAGUGUUAAUGAACUUCACCAUCACUGCCUUCUUGAAUUAAUUUUCAUUAUCUUGCCUCUUCACUGGUUUUUAAUGUGUAUGCCCUUCACUAUCUCUGCCAGCCUCCAUUCAUUCCCAUGAUUGAGCAUUCCCCGCCACUUUGUAACCUGUCUCCAUUCUCCAUGAUCCCUCACCUGUUUCAGCACCACUGAAUAUUGUCACUAACUUGGAAGCCAGCCGCACCUUGCAUGGGGAAGUCCCCUCCCUGGAGUCCAGCAAGUCCCAGUGACAGAACCCAUACCAUUUCCCCAGAUAGCUUUGCUCCUCGUUCAUUUUGGCCUUUCUCCCUUUGGUUGGGGGCCAUUUGCCUCUCCCUUCUCCCCUGCUGUGCCUUUCCUCUCAGAUUAUUGACCAGUUUGAGGAGAACAUGCCUGUAUUAAGGGCCGAGGUGGAAGAGCUCCAAGCCCAGACCCGGGAACCCCGAGAGGUCAUAUUUGAGGAUGUUCUGCUUCGGA